GGACUCCGUCUCAAAAAAAUAAAAAAAAUAAAAAAAAAGGAAAGUGAGAUAGAAAUAAUUUUUUAAAACUUACUAUUCAAAAUUUGCAAAACUAAAUAAGAGUAAAAGAAAUUUACAUUUUGUCCCUGGAUUCACAGAAGACAAAAACAUUGUGUGGGAAAGCUGGAGUUGAGGACGAACGAGAUUCUGAAAAUAAAAAUCCCUGGUACAUAAGCCAAAAUUUCAGAGUCAACUACAGAUUUUCAAAGGCUAUGAAAUAGGUAACCUCAAGCCACCGACUCCAAUAGAUAAAAGGAACCAGGUAAUAUCUGUGUUCCAGGGAGAAAGAAUAGAAAACUGGCUGAGUUCUAUCACUGACAAAACUUAGUGCGAAGGAGGGAUCUGGAAGGCGGGAGGGUGAAGGGAUCCCCGGCUUGGAGGGUGGGGAGGGGCUGUGCUUCGGCCUCCCCCUCCUACUGCCCCUCCCCAACAAAGGAGCCCUUUGUGAUGUGAAGCCCCAGCUCUGUGAUGCGGGCCUGGGCCCCAGUCCCUAGUCUCCACGAGGAUGCCCAGAGCUCAGUUGCUAGAAAGCAAUGCGCCUAUUCACAUGGAGAAUCUUCCCUUUCCUCUAAAAUUACUUAGUGCCUCAUCACUAAACACCCCCAGCUCCACACCAUGGGUGUUGGAUAUCUUCCUCACCUUGGUGUUUGCCCUGGGGCUCUUCUUCCUAUUACUCCCCUACUUCUCUUACCUCCGUUGUGACAACCCACCCUCACCAUCGCCUAGGAAGAGAAAGCGUCAUCUUGUCUCCCAGCGUCAUCUUGUCUCCCAGUGUCCAACAGGGCGGAGGGGGAGGCCCAGAGGCAGGAUGAAAAACCACAGUCUGAGAGCUUGUAGAGAGUGCCCGAGAGGCCUGGAGGAGACUUGGGACCUGCUUUCACAACUGCAGAGCCUCCUGGGGCCACACCUUGAAAAAGGUGACUUUGGUCAGCUCUCUGGUCCAGACCCGCCAGGUGAGGUGGGCAAAAGAACACCUGAUGGAGCCUCCCGGUCCUCUCAUGAGCCUAUGGAAGAUGCUGCUCCCAUUGUCUCCCCGUUAGCUUCCCCGGAUCCUCGAACCAAGCAUCCUCAGGAUCUGGCCUCCACCCCACCACCAGGCCCAAUGACCACCUCAGUCUCCUCCCUAAGUGCCUCCCAGCCACCAGAACCUUCCCUUCUCCUAGAACGCCCCUCACCCGAGCCACCUGCACUUUUCCCUCACCCACCACACACCCCUGAUCCUCUGGCCUGCUCUCCACCUCCUCCGAAAGGCUUCACUCCUCCUCCCCUGCGGGACUCCACUCUGUUAACACCAUCUCACUGUGACUCAGUGGCACUUCCACUGGACACCGUCCCUCAAAGCUUGUCUCCACGUGAGGAUUUGGCGGCUUCUGUCCCAGCCAUCUCAGGCCUUGGCGGCUCAAACAGUCAAGUUUCUGCCCUCUCCUGGUCGCAGGAGACUACCAAAACCUGGUGCAUCUUCAACUCGUCAGUCCAGCAAGAUCAUCUUUCCCGCCAAAGGGACACCACAAUGUCCCCACUGCUUUUCCAGGCCCAGCCCCUGUCCCAUCUGGGGCCUGAGUCCCAACCCUUUAUUUCAUCCACACCCCAAUUCCGGCCCACACCUAUGGCUCAGGCCGAGGCUCAGGCCCAUCUUCAAUCCUCUUUCCCAGUCCUAUCUCCUGCUUUUCUAUCCCCGAUGAAGAACACUGGAGUAGCUUGCCCUGCGUCGCAGAAUAAAGUGCAAGCUCUCUCCUUACCUGAAACUCAGCACCCUGAAAGGCCUUUGUUGAGGAAACAACUAGAAGGUGGGUUGGCUUUACCCUCUAGGGUCCAAAAAUCUCAGGACGUCUUUAGUGUCUCCACUCCUAACCUUCCCCAGGAAAGACUGACAUCCAUUCUGCCUGAGAACUUUCCAGUCAGUCCUGAACUCUGGAGACAACUGGAGCAAUACAUGGGGCAACGUGGAAGGAUCCAAGAGUCUCUGGAUCUGAUGCAGCUUCAGGAUGAAUUGCCAGGGACAAGUCAGGCCAAGGGCAAACCCAGGCCCUGGCAGUCCUCCACGUCCACAGGUGAAAGCAGCAAGGAGGCACAGACGGUGAAGUUCCAGCUAGAGAGGGACCCAUGCCCACAUCUGGGGCAAAUUCUGGGUGAGACCCCACAAAAUCUAUCCAGGGGCAUGGAAAGCUUCCCAGGGAAGGUUCUGGGGGCGACCUCUGAGGAGUCAGAAAGGAACCUGAGGAAGCCCUUGAGGAGUGACUCAGGAAGUGAUUUAUUAAGACGCACAGAGAGGAAUCAUAUAGAAAACAUCCUGAAAGCCCACAUGGGCAGAAAGUUGGGCCAGACCAACGAGGGCUUGAUCCCCGUGAGUGUGCGUCGAUCCUGGCUUGCUGUCAACCAGGCUUUUCCCGUAUCCAACACCCACGUGAAAACCAGCAAUCUAGCAGCCCCGAAAAGUAGGAAAGCCUGUGUAAACACAGCCCAGGUGCUUUCCUUCCUUGAGCUGUGUACUCAGCAGGUGCUGGAAGCCCAUAUUGUGAGGUUUUGGGCCAAACACAGGUGGGGUCUACCCCUCAGGGUCCUCAAGCCCAUUCAGUGCUUUCAACUGGAAAAGGUUUCAUCCUUGUCCCUUAUACAGCUUGCUGGUCCCUCCUCAGACACCUGCGAAUCUGGGGCUGGCUCAAAAGUUGAGGUGGCCACGCUCCUUGGAGAGCCACCAAUGGCAAGUCUGAGAAAGCAAGUGCUGACCAAACCAUCUGUUCACAUGCCAGAGAGGCUUCAGGCCUCCUCACCUGCAUGUAAGCAGUUCCAGAGGGCCCCGCGAGGGAUCCCAUCUUCAAAUGAUCAUGGGUCCUUGAAGGCUCCUACAGCUGGACAGGAGGGCAGGUGGCCAUCUAAGCCCCUCACAUACAGCCUCAAAGGCAGCACCCAGCAGAGCAGGAGCUUAGGAGCCCAAUCUUCAAGGGCUGGAGAGACCAGGGAGGCAGUGCCACAACCCACAGUCCCCUUGGGAACCUGUAUGAGAGCAAACCUCCAAGCCACAAGUGAGGAUGUGCGUGGUUUCAAGGCUCCAGGCGCCAGCAAAAGCUCUCUACUCCCUAGAAUGUCUGUCUCCCAAGACCCAAGAAAGCUGUGUCUCAUGGAGGAGGCUGUUAGUGAAUUUGAGCCUGGAAUGGCCACGAAGUCAGAGACCCAGCCUCAAGUUUCUGCCGCUGUUGUGCUCCUUCCAGAUGGGCAAGCAUCUGUUGUGCCCCAUGCUUCAGAGAAUUUGGCUUCUCAAGUGCCCCAGGGCCAUCUCCAGAGCACGCCUACUGGGAACAUGCAGGCUUCCCAGGAGCUAUGUGACCUCAUGUCAGCCAGAAGGAGUAACAUGGGGCACAAGGAGCCCAGGAACCCAAACUGUCAAGGCUCAUGCAAGAGCCAAAGCCCAAUGUUUCCCCCUACUCACAAGAGGGAGAACUCUAGGAAGCCCAACUUAGAAAAACAUGAAGAAAUGUUUCAAGGAUUGAGGACUCCUCAACUUACCCCAGGCAGAAAAACAGAAGACACCCGUCAGAAUGAAGGCGUCCAGCUACUGCCAUCAAAGAAACAGCCUCCUUCAAUAAGCCACUUUGGAGAAAACAUCAAGCAAUUUUUUGAGACGAUUUUUUCAAAGAAAGAAAGGAAGCCAGCACCAGUCACUGCUGAGAGCCAAAAAACAGUAAAAAACAGAUCAUGCGUGUACGGCAGCAGUGCUGAAGCUGAGAGGCUCAUGACAGCAGUUGGACAGAUACCGGAGGAGAACAUGUCACUUUGCCAUGCGCGCCAUGCCUCGAAGGUAAAUCAGCAAAGACAGCAGUUUCAAGCCCCAGUCUGUGGGUUUCCCUGCAACCACAGACACCCGUUCUACUCAGACCACAGCAGAAUGCUGAGCUAUGCAGCCAGCAGUCAACAAGCCACUCUCAAGAACCAGAGUCGUCCCAACAGAGACAGACAAAUCAGAGAUCAGCAGCCCUUGAAAAGUGUCCGGUGCAACAAUGAGCAAUGGGGCCUGCGACAUCCCCAACUCUUGCUCCCCAAGAAAGCUGUAUCCCCAGUCAGUCCCCCUCAGCACCGGCCGAAGACACCCAGUGCCUCCAGCCACCAUCACCACUGACCAAGGCACUGUCUUUUUCAGGGAGGUAUCUAAUUUGGUCAGUCACAAAUUCCUUUUUAGCCUUCCCUAGAGAAAAACAAGUCACCAAGAAAAAAUUCACUCUAUGUAGAGGAAAAGUAUUUUCUCUCAUGUUAGUACACGCAGAACAUUUAAUAUUCCACAAUAUAUACGGUUUUUUAUUCA